AUGCUCGGGAGCGUGGUUGAGCGGCUGGCGCGGUUGUCCUGGAGCAGGGGCGCAGGUAGGUGAUGGCUGCUGCCGCACCCCUGCCCUCCAGCUCGGUUGUCACGGGGAUCACCCCUUUGCAUUUCCUCGGGGCGUGGCGGGAUGUGGCCAGGGCUGCGAGCAGUUCGGGGGACACUGGAGACUUGGGGAACGGCGUAUGGCCUCCCCCUGGUCUCCUGCCGCCGCCUCCUAGGCCUGUGAGCCCGGGGUCUGGUGACGGGGUCGUGUGCUGGAAGACAGGCAGGUAGGAUCGGGAUGAGCGGGCAGGGACGCGGGCUACGUCCCUGGCCGCGGCCGCCAGGGGGCGCUGCGCCCGCGGGCCGUGGGUGUGGGUCGCGCUCGCCUGGGCAGGCCGGAGCGGGCUGUGGGAACGCCCUAGGGCCCGGGCAUCCCAGGCGAAGCGGGUCUGAGAGAAACGCCCACCUGGGAGGCUGUGCAGCGGGUGGCUCGGGGCACCCUGCUCAACCCGCAGCGGAGCCGCCAGCGACCUUCGAAGUAAGUCAUCCCCUUCGUUUUUGCAAGCGGGUAAAUGGAGGUACGUGACAUAAGCACGCGCAGCAAAGCCGUGGCUGUGCCGGGAACGCAGCCCAGAUCUCUCCACGGUCAUCCAGUGCUCUUUUCGCUUCUGCCACACAGAGCCGCGGGUGGCUUUGUGUUUAUCACACAGGGGCCAUUUGGUUUCUGCACAGACGGAGAGGCUGGAGGCAGGUGGGCACAGGAACGACGGGGAAAGUUUCAGGAGGUCUUGGAGGAGGAGAUGGCUAGGUUUUACUGUGGUCCGCAGCGUGUAUGAAAGCUUGAGGGCCUGGAGGUGAUGGAAACCUACUCAUGAGUGUUGGGAUGACUGCAGCUUGCACACACCAGUCUGGUAAUCCCGUGCAACUCUCCUCCUGCCAUGCAGUUGAAUCAGUAUCAUUGUGCAGGGAGAGUGUCUACACUUUUAUCAGUGGAAAGAGAAUCUUGGUAAAAAAGGGCAGCUGACUAAGUGGCCUCAACCCUAUUGGGCACUUCUUUGGGGUUCUCCCACGUUGAUUAUUCUGCUUCUACCCUUGUACAUGUCUGGACAACAGGUUUGUUUUUUACAAACAAAAAUCCCUUCUCUUUCUUCCUCUCUUGAUAGCUGAGGCAAGUGAGCAUUUAAAAAAGAUAUUCCAACAACUUUAAAGGAGGACACGAGAAGAUAGGGAAAUAUAAAUAGUAUCAGUAAAAUGGCUGGCCUGGGGAUCCAUCCUUGCUUGCUUGCUUGCUUCAGACUGGGGCUUUGUUUCUUUCCAAACCUGUCAGGAUUCCCAGCUCUUCGCCGGCCUCCACGUGGGGUGCCCUCUUUUAUGUUCCAGAUACACAGACGAUGGUGUCCUUAUGUUCAAGGCCACAGACAGUAACUUUGUGCCUACUUUGGGCCUGCCUGCUCUCCUGAUUGUGCCUCUUUUUCCAGGAAAGUAGAGAUGAGUGUGUUAGAGAUAAUGGAACACUGUUCCCCACACCCUUCAUACAUAGAAUAACUUAGUCCCUUAGGAUAGUUUAGCAGUGUCUACCACAGCAGUCACUGUAGGCACAAAACAGUCAUUAUUUGUGUCAUAACAGGGAAGUCGUUUUGUCCCUGCCUCUCUCUGCUCCUGUGCUCCACUGAUUCUACUUCAUCCUUUGAAAUAAAAGUGGUUGAAAGAAUCUUUGGUUAUCAUGGGUGCUUAGAUAAUUAAGAUUAUGUUCGUGUUCUUCUUGAUGUGGCAUUUCAUAUUGUGGAUGAGUUCCAGUGACCUCCUCUGUUUCAAACUGCUCACCGCCCCAACCCCCACCUUUUAAAAAGGUAGUACUAAUCUUUUCCUCUUCCAGAUAAUCAGCUAAGCUAGGGAACCCUUGAAGGGGAAGGUUAGAAUUUCGUGAUUCCCGUAAGAAGGUUACUCUGAUCUACAGCUACAGCUCAACACUGGGGACACUGGCAGAUGCCAGGUCUGUUUAUAGUUUAGCCUUAAUGAGGUCUCAAUGACGUGAUUGCUGCACUCUGGCUUGGUGAGCCGCUGUUCUUUAUGGUGUAGUUUGUCAUUGGACAAGGUGACUUUUUUUUUUUUUUUAAAGAUAAGUAACAGCUAUAUCAACUUAGGGUACUUGAACCAGAAUUCUGAAAGGCAAGAAAUCAAGCUUUCUUUGGACUGGAAACCUGUCUUUGCAUAGGAGAUUUAGUCCUUUUUAUUCAGAGGAUUAGAAUUCUGAUGUGAAACUAACAGUCUGUGAGCCCUGGAACCUCCACUCAGAGAAGAUGAAGGAUAUCGACAUAGGAAAAGAGUAUAUCAUCCCCAGUCCUGGGUAUAGAAGUGUGAGGGAGAGAACCAGCACUUCUGGGACGCACAGAGACCGUGAAGAUUCCAAGUUCAGGAGAACUCGACCGUUGGAAUGCCAAGAUGCCUUGGAAACAGCAGCCCGAGCCGAGGGCCUCUCUCUUGAUGCCUCCAUGCAUUCUCAGCUCAGAAUCCUGGAUGAGGAGCAUCCCAAGGGAAAGUACCAUCAUGGCUUGAGUGCUCUGAAGCCCAUCCGGACUACUUCCAAACACCAGCACCCAGUGGACAAUGCUGGGCUUUUUUCCUGUAUGACUUUUUCGUGGCUUUCUUCUCUGGCCCGUGUGGCCCACAAGAAGGGGGAGCUCUCAAUGGAAGACGUGUGGUCUCUGUCCAAGCACGAGUCUUCUGACGUGAACUGCAGAAGACUAGAGAGACUGUGGCAAGAAGAGCUGAAUGAAGUUGGGCCAGACGCUGCUUCCCUGCGAAGGGUUGUGUGGAUCUUCUGCCGCACCAGGCUCAUCCUGUCCAUCGUGUGCCUGAUGAUCACGCAGCUGGCUGGCUUCAGUGGACCAGCCUUCAUGGUGAAACACCUCUUGGAGUAUACCCAGGCAACAGAGUCUAACCUGCAGUACAGCUUGUUGUUAGUGCUGGGCCUCCUCCUGACGGAAAUCGUGCGGUCUUGGUCGCUUGCACUGACUUGGGCAUUGAAUUACCGAACCGGUGUCCGCUUGCGGGGGGCCAUCCUAACCAUGGCAUUUAAGAAGAUCCUUAAGUUAAAGAACAUUAAAGAGAAAUCCCUGGGUGAGCUCAUCAACAUUUGCUCCAACGAUGGGCAGAGAAUGUUUGAGGCAGCAGCCGUUGGCAGCCUGCUGGCUGGAGGACCCGUUGUUGCCAUCUUAGGCAUGAUUUAUAAUGUAAUUAUUCUGGGACCAACAGGCUUCCUGGGAUCAGCUGUUUUUAUCCUCUUUUACCCAGCAAUGAUGUUUGCAUCACGGCUCACAGCAUAUUUCAGGAGAAAAUGCGUGGCCGCCACGGAUGAACGUGUCCAGAAGAUGAAUGAAGUUCUUACUUACAUUAAAUUUAUCAAAAUGUAUGCCUGGGUCAAAGCAUUUUCUCAGAGUGUUCAAAAAAUCCGCGAGGAGGAGCGUCGGAUAUUGGAAAAAGCUGGGUACUUCCAGAGCAUCACUGUGGGUGUGGCUCCCAUUGUGGUGGUGAUUGCCAGCGUGGUGACCUUCUCUGUUCAUAUGACCCUGGGCUUCGAUCUGACAGCAGCACAGGCUUUCACAGUGGUGACAGUCUUCAAUUCCAUGACUUUUGCUUUGAAAGUAACACCGUUUUCAGUAAAGUCCCUCUCAGAAGCCUCAGUGGCUGUUGACAGAUUUAAGAGUUUGUUUCUAAUGGAAGAGGUUCACAUGAUAAAGAACAAACCAGCCAGUCCUCACAUCAAGAUAGAGAUGAAAAAUGCCACCUUGGCAUGGGACUCCUCCCACUCCAGUAUCCAGAACUCGCCCAAGCUGACCCCCAAAAUGAAAAAAGACAAGAGGGCUUCCAGGGGCAAGAAAGAGAAGGUGAGGCAGCUGCAGCGCACUGAGCAUCAGGCGGUGCUGGCAGAGCAGAAAGGCCACCUCCUCCUGGACAGUGACGAGCGGCCCAGUCCCGAAGAGGAAGAAGGCAAGCACAUCCACCUGGGCCACCUGCGCUUACAGAGGACACUGCACAGCAUCGAUCUGGAGAUCCAAGAGGGUAAACUGGUUGGAAUCUGUGGCAGUGUGGGAAGUGGAAAAACCUCUCUCAUUUCAGCCAUUUUAGGCCAGAUGACGCUUCUAGAGGGCAGCAUUGCAAUCAGUGGAACCUUCGCUUAUGUGGCCCAGCAGGCCUGGAUCCUCAAUGCUACUCUGAGAGACAACAUCCUGUUUGGGAAGGAAUAUGAUGAAGAAAGAUACAACUCUGUGCUGAACAGCUGCUGCCUGAGGCCUGACCUGGCCAUUCUUCCCAGCAGCGACCUGACGGAGAUUGGAGAGCGAGGAGCCAACCUGAGCGGUGGGCAGCGCCAGAGGAUCAGCCUUGCCCGGGCCUUGUAUAGUGACAGGAGCAUCUACAUCCUGGACGACCCCCUCAGUGCCUUAGAUGCCCAUGUGGGCAACCACAUCUUCAAUAGUGCUAUCCGGAAACAUCUCAAGUCCAAGACAGUUCUGUUUGUUACCCACCAGUUACAGUACCUGGUUGACUGUGAUGAAGUGAUCUUCAUGAAAGAGGGCUGUAUUACGGAAAGAGGCACCCAUGAGGAACUGAUGAAUUUAAAUGGUGACUAUGCUACCAUUUUUAAUAACCUGUUGCUGGGAGAGACACCGCCAGUUGAGAUCAAUUCAAAAAAGGAAACCAGUGGUUCACAGAAGAAGUCACAAGACAAGGGUCCUAAAACAGGAUCAGUAAAGAAGGAAAAAGCAGUAAAGCCAGAGGAAGGGCAGCUUGUGCAGCUGGAAGAGAAAGGGCAGGGUUCAGUGCCCUGGUCAGUAUAUGGUGUCUACAUCCAGGCUGCUGGGGGCCCCUUGGCAUUCCUGGUUAUUAUGGCCCUUUUCAUGCUGAAUGUAGGCAGCACCGCCUUCAGCACCUGGUGGUUGAGUUACUGGAUCAAGCAAGGAAGCGGGAACACCACUGUGACUCGAGGGAACGAGACCUCGGUGAGUGACAGCAUGAAGGACAAUCCUCAUAUGCAGUACUAUGCCAGCAUCUACGCCCUCUCCAUGGCAGUCAUGCUGAUCCUGAAAGCCAUUCGAGGAGUUGUCUUUGUCAAGGGCACGCUGCGAGCUUCCUCCCGGCUGCAUGACGAGCUUUUCCGAAGGAUCCUUCGAAGCCCUAUGAAGUUUUUUGACACGACCCCCACAGGGAGGAUUCUCAACAGGUUUUCCAAAGACAUGGAUGAAGUUGACGUGCGGCUGCCGUUCCAGGCCGAGAUGUUCAUCCAGAACGUUAUCCUGGUGUUCUUCUGUGUGGGAAUGAUCGCAGGAGUCUUCCCGUGGUUCCUUGUGGCAGUGGGGCCCCUUGUCAUCCUCUUUUCAGUCCUGCACAUUGUCUCCAGGGUCCUGAUUCGGGAGCUGAAGCGUCUGGACAAUAUCACGCAGUCACCUUUCCUCUCCCACAUCACGUCCAGCAUACAGGGCCUUGCCACCAUCCACGCCUACAAUAAAGGGCAGGAGUUUCUGCACAGAUACCAGGAGCUGCUGGAUGACAACCAAGCUCCUUUUUUUUUGUUUACGUGUGCGAUGCGGUGGCUGGCUGUGCGGCUGGACCUCAUCAGCAUCGCCCUCAUCACCACCACGGGGCUGAUGAUCGUUCUUAUGCACGGGCAGAUUCCCCCAGCCUAUGCGGGUCUCGCCAUCUCUUAUGCUGUCCAGUUAACGGGGCUGUUCCAGUUUACGGUCAGACUGGCAUCUGAGACAGAAGCUCGAUUCACCUCGGUGGAGAGGAUCAAUCACUACAUUAAGACUCUGUCCUUGGAAGCACCUGCCAGAAUUAAGAACAAGGCUCCCUCCCCUGACUGGCCCCAGGAGGGAGAGGUGACCUUUGAGAACGCAGAGAUGAGGUACCGAGAAAACCUCCCUCUCGUCCUAAAGAAAGUAUCCUUCACGAUCAAACCUAAAGAGAAGAUUGGCAUUGUGGGGCGGACAGGAUCAGGGAAGUCCUCGCUGGGGAUGGCCCUCUUCCGUCUGGUGGAGUUAUCUGGAGGCUGCAUCAAGAUUGAUGGAGUGAGAAUCAGUGAUAUUGGCCUUGCCGACCUCCGAAGCAAACUCUCUAUCAUUCCUCAAGAGCCGGUGCUGUUCAGUGGCACUGUCAGAUCAAAUUUGGACCCCUUCAACCAGUACACUGAAGACCAGAUUUGGGAUGCCCUGGAGAGGACACACAUGAAAGAAUGUAUUGCUCAGCUACCUCUGAAACUUGAAUCUGAAGUGAUGGAGAAUGGGGAUAACUUCUCAGUGGGGGAACGGCAGCUCUUGUGCAUAGCUAGAGCCCUGCUCCGCCACUGUAAGAUUCUGAUUUUAGAUGAAGCCACAGCUGCCAUGGACACAGAGACAGACUUAUUGAUUCAAGAGACCAUCCGAGAAGCAUUUGCAGACUGUACCAUGCUGACCAUUGCCCAUCGCCUGCACACGGUUCUAGGCUCCGAUAGGAUUAUGGUGCUGGCCCAGGGACAGGUGGUGGAGUUUGACACCCCAUCGGUCCUUCUGUCCAACGACAGUUCCCGAUUCUAUGCCAUGUUUGCUGCUGCAGAGAACAAGGUCGCUGUCAAGGGCUGACUCCUCCCUGUUGACGAAGUCUCUUUUCUUUAGAGCAUUGCCAUUCCCUGCCUGGGGCGGGCCCCUCAUCGCGUCCUCCUACCGAAACCUUGCCUUUCUCGAUUUUAUCUUUCGCACAGCAGUUCCGGAUUGGCUUGUGUGUUUCACUUUUAGGGAGAGUCAUAUUUUGAUUAUUGUAUUUAUUCCAUAUUCAUGUAAACAAAAUUUAGUUUUUGUUCUUAAUUGCACUCUAAAAGGUUCAGGGAACCGUUAUUAUAAUUGUAUCAGAGGCCUAUAAUGAAGCUUUAUACGUGUAGCUAUAUCUAUAUAUAAUUCUGUACAUAGCCUAUAUUUACAGUGAAAAUGUAAGCUGUUUAUUUUAUAUUAAAAUAAGCACUGUGCUAAUAACAGUGCAUAUUCCUUUCUAUCAUUUUUGUACAGUUUGCUGUACUAGAGAUCUGGUUUUGCUAUUAGACUGUAGGAAGAGUAGCAUUUCAUUCUUCUCUAGCUGGUGGUUUCACGGUGCCAGGUUUUCUGGGUGUCCAAAGGAAGACGUGUGGCAAUAGUGGGCCCUCCGACAGCCCCCUCUGCCGCCUCCCCACGGCCGCUCCAGGGGUGGCUGGAGACGGGUGGGCGGCUGGAGACCAUGCAGAGCGCCGUGAGUUCUCAGGGCUCCUGCCUUCUGUCCUGGUGUCACUUACUGUUUCUGUCAGGAGAGCAGCGGGGCGAAGCCCAGGCCCCUUUUCACUCCCUCCAUCAAGAAUGGGGAUCACAGAGACAUUCCUCCGAGCCGGGGAGUUUCUUUCCUGCCUUCUUCUUUUUGCUGUUGUUUCUAAACAAGAAUCAGUCUAUCCACAGAGAGUCCCACUGCCUCAGGUUCCUAUGGCUGGCCACUGCACAGAGCUCUCCAGCUCCAAGACCUGUUGGUUCCAAGCCCUGGAGCCAACUGCUGCUUUUUGAGGUGGCACUUUUUCAUUUGCCUAUUCCCACACCUCCACAGUUCAGUGGCAGGGCUCAGGAUUUCGUGGGUCUGUUUUCCUUUCUCACCGCAGUCGUCGCACAGUCUCUCUCUCUCUCUCCCCUCAAAGUCUGCAACUUUAAGCAGCUCUUGCUAAUCAGUGUCUCACACUGGCGUAGAAGUUUUUGUACUGUAAAGAGACCUACCUCAGGUUGCUGGUUGCUGUGUGGUUUGGUGUGUUCCCGCAAACCCCCUUUGUGCUGUGGGGCUGGUAGCUCAGGUGGGCGUGGUCACUGCUGUCAUCAAUUGAAUGGUCAGCGUUGCAUGUCGUGACCAACUAGACAUUCUGUCGCCUUAGCAUGUUUGCUGAACACCUUGUGGAAGCAAAAAUCUGAAAAUGUGAAUAAAAUUAUUUUGGAUUUUGUAAAA